AGUCUCUUUUCCGGUUAGCGCGGCGUGAGAAGCCAUGAGCAGCAAAGUCUCUCGCGACACCCUGUACGAGGCGGUGCGGGAAGUCCUGCACGGGAACCAGCGCAAGCGCCGCAAGUUCCUGGAGACGGUGGAGUUGCAGAUCAGCUUGAAGAACUAUGAUCCCCAGAAGGACAAGCGCUUCUCGGGCACCGUCAGGCUUAAGUCCACUCCCCGCCCUAAGUUCUCUGUGUGUGUCCUGGGGGACCAGCAGCACUGUGACGAGGCUAAGGCCGUGGAUAUCCCCCACAUGGACAUCGAGGCGCUGAAAAAACUCAACAAGAAUAAAAAACUGGUCAAGAAGCUGGCCAAGAAGUAUGAUGCGUUUUUGGCCUCAGAGUCUCUGAUCAAGCAGAUUCCACGAAUCCUCGGCCCAGGUUUAAAUAAGGCAGGAAAGUUCCCUUCCCUGCUCACACACAACGAAAACAUGGUGGCCAAAGUGGAUGAGGUGAAGUCCACAAUCAAGUUCCAAAUGAAGAAGGUGUUAUGUCUGGCUGUAGCUGUUGGUCACGUGAAGAUGACAGACGAUGAGCUUGUGUAUAACAUUCACCUGGCUGUCAACUUCUUGGUGUCAUUGCUCAAGAAAAACUGGCAGAAUGUCCGGGCCUUAUAUAUCAAGAGCACCAUGGGCAAGCCCCAGCGCCUAUAUUAAGGCACAUUUGAAUAAAUUCUAUUACCAGUU